AUCUAUAUACAGAGAAGAAACACAGUAAAAUAUUAACUUAGGAUAGAAGUACAUAUUCUAUAUAUGCUCCCGAAUUAUGUUUAAUGUUCUUAGAGUUAGACUGUUACUUUAGUUCCUUAUAAAAAUGCCUUCACAGAUCUAUGGUUUAACAUUAUACCUUCUUGGCUUUUUAUUUGAGGUUCAAAGUCCUUACCACAGGGCCCAGCAGGACCUACCUUCUGGCCUCCUCUCCAAUUUCAUCUCCUAAACUUUUCCCUAUUGCUCCCUCUACUUUCGGUUCCCAUAUACCAGGGGCAAUAUGACCUUGGAGCCUCAUGGUUCUCUUGGCCUGGAACUCUCUUUUCCCAAAUUAAUUGUACAGCUUGCACUCUUACUUCACUCAGGUUUCCAUUUAGAUGUCAAAGGUCUUCCUUGACCAUCCAGUCUACAAACGGCCCACUCAUUCUCUCACUACCCCACCCCCUGCCUCACCUGUCAUCUCUGUCCUCUUUAUGUUUUUAUUUUUCAAAGUAUAUCAUGACUUGAUAUACUUUAAAUGAUACAUUACUUAUCAUUUAAAAAAUAUCUGCCUACUUACACUAAUAUGUGAGCUCAGUGAGUACAUACACUGUGUCUUAUCCAUUUUUGGGCCCAAGCUUCUACAACACGCCUGGCACACGGUUAAUAUAAAUGCUGCUGAAUAAAUGCUGAAUGAAUGAAGGAAGGAAUAAAGGAAUGAACAAACAAAUGAAGGGUCCAUAUCAUGGGACACAGGAAGAAUGUGUCUAAAUUUAUAAACCUGCUAUGAUUACAGCCCAAGUAUGUUAUUUGAUGACGCUAAGUUAAGGGUCAAAAAAUAAAGAUAAAUAAAUUACUAAUAUCAUAUAAAUUCUUACUUAUAGUGCUAAGAAUGUAUAUGUCUUUUUUUAUUAAAGAACUGGGUUUUUGUUUUUAUUUUUUUGAGAUUGGGUCACACUAUGUUGCUCAGGUUGGUCUUGAACUUCUAGGCUCAAGUGAUCCUCCUGCCUCAGCCUCCUGAGUAGCUGGGAUUACAGUUGCACACCACCAUGCCUGGCUCCAAACUGAUGAUAUUUUUAAAAAAUUAAGUGAGAGGAGAUAGGGACAAGAUAGAACCAACCCUCACCCAACAAUUAGAGAAUAUAUAUUCUGCCCAAGCACAGAUAGAAAAAUUUAUAACUUGACCAUUGUGACAGGCUGAAAAGUGGCUCCCAAAAGGUAUGUAUGUCCUAAUCCCUGGAACUUGUGAAUGCACCCUCUGUGCCAAAAAGUAAAAGAAAAAAGGAAAGCAAAGGUAUUCAUAGACGUGAUUAAGGAUCUUAAGAUGGGGAGGUUAUCCUGGAUCCUAGUGUGCCCUAAAUGCAAUCACAUAUAUUCUUAAAAGAGAGGGGCAUAGGAGGAGAAGGUAAUGUGACUGAGGAGGCAGAGAUCGGAAUGAUGGGGCCACAAACCAAAGGAUGCUGGCAGCCAUCAGAUUAAGGAAUGGAUUCUCCCCAAGAGCCUAUGGAGGGAAGGUGGUCCUGCUGACAUUGUGAUGUCAGCCCAGUGAUACUACUUUCAGAACUCCAGAACUGAGACAAUACAUUUUUGUAGUUUUAAGCCAUCAAAUAUGUUAUUAUUUUUUAGGGAACAAAUACAAGUUUCAAUAAAUUUCAGAGUUAGUUUCACUUAGAAUUCUUUCUGACCAGGAGGCAAGAGUCAGAAACCAGUUAAAACAAGAAGAAAAAAAAAGCAAAAAAGAAAAAUAAAUUCUGACAUAUUUGGACAUUAACAAACACUUCUAAAUAAUACAUGGACAAAAGAAAAACCAUAAUAGAAAAAUAUAAAAAUACUUAGAAGUGAACAAAACUAAAAUCCUUCAAAUUAAACCUAUAAGAUACACUAAAAGCAGUGCUUUGCUUGAAAUUUAAAAGCUUACAUUAGAAAAUAAGAAAGCUGUCCAGGCACGGUGGCUCAUGCCUGUAAUCCCAGCACUUUGGGAGGCCGAGUGGGUAGAUCACCUAAAGUCAGGAGUUCGAGACCAGCCUGGCCAGCAUGAUGAAACCCUGUCUCUACUAAAAAUACAAAAAUUAGCCAGGCGUAUGGCUAUUGCCAGUAAUCCUAGCUACUGGGGAGGCUGAGGCAGGAGAAUUGCCUGAACCAGGGAGGCAGAGGUUGCAGUGAGCUGAGAUCAUGCCACUGCACUCUAGCCUGGGCAACCGAGCAAGACUCCAUCUCAAAAAAAAGAAAGAUUAGGCCGGGCGCAGUGGCUCACGCCUGUAAUCCCAGCACUUUGGGAGGCUGAGGCAGGCAGAUCACGAGGUCAGGAGUUUGAGACCAGCCUGGCCAAUACGGUGAAACCCCAUCUCUACUAAAAAAUACAAAAAUGAGCUAGGCGUGGUAGCACCCUCCUGUAAUCCCAGCUACUUGGGAGGCUGAGGGAGGAUAAUCGCUGGAACCCAGGAGGCGGAGGUUGCAGUGAGCCAAGAUUGUGCCACUGCACUCCAGCCUGGGCAACAGAGCAAGACUCCAUCUCAAAAAAAAAAAAAAAGAAAGAAAGAAAUAUUAGCAAUAAGCUAACAUGUCCAACUUAAGAAGUUAGAAGAAAGACAAUAAAUCAAAGAAAGAGCAAAAAAAAAGAAAGUAAAGAGCAAAAAUUAAUAAAAUCAAAUACAGAAGUUAUAAUAGAGGGGGCCAACAAAGCCAAAAGUUUUUUUUUUUUUAAAAGACACAAGGCAUAAAAAUGAUAUGAAGAAUGAAAAAGAAAAUAUUAUGACUACAAGAUAUAUUAAAACCUAGGUAAAUAACUUAUAAAAAUCAAAAAGUCCUAAAGCUGUUACCAAAACUAAAUUGGUUACUAAAAAUCUUCUCACAAAGAAAAUGCUACGCCAAAAUUGUUUUACAGGCAAGUUUUACCAAAUGACCAAGGAAAGAUCAUACCACUCUUAUAUAAACUUCUCUAAAAAACUAAAAAAGGAACAUUAACCUAACUAAUUUAGUAAACCAGUAUAUCACUAAUAAAAAAACAAAAUAAGAACAGUAUGAGAGAAGAAAAUUAUAAGCCAGUAUCAUUCACGAACAUAGAUGCAAAAAUCGUAAAAUAUUAGCAAAUGGAAUCCAGAGGGGAAUAAAAAAUAAUGAGUCAUAACCAAACCGAGUUUAUUUCAUGAAUGCACAUCUAUAUUGUUGAGAGAUUUGUGCCAAAGUAUUUAAGGGUAAAUAAUAUAUCUAUAAUUUUCCUUGAAAUGGUUCAGAGGGGGAAAAAAGAGGGAGAAAUGAAGCAGAUAUAGCAAAAUGUUAACAACUGUUGCACAUAUGUAUCGAGAGGUAUAGGAAUGUUCAUUGUCUAAACAGCAAAAAAACUUGGAAAAAAUCAUAAAGAUAAUUAACUAUGGUUAGACAAAAUACCAGAGAUGUUUGAUAUGUAAUAUUGAGUGAAAAAGCAAGCUGCAGAGACUACGUACAGAAUGAUACCAUAUUUAUAAAACUCAGAACUAUGCAAUACUAAAAGCGACAUUGCUGAGAUUGAUAUGUAACAUAUACGCUGAAACUACUUUUUAAAAAGGAAGGAAAUGAUGAACACAAAACCCAUAAUAGUUCCUCCUGGAACUGUGUCGAGGAGGCAGAGGAGUGGGUAGGGAAAGAGCACAGACUGGUAAAGUUUUGCUUCUUAAAUUAGGGAGGAGCUCCCUGGUAUUCAUUUCCCCACUGUGCUUUACAAUUUGCAUAUGUUAUAUGUACAUAUCAAAUAUUACAUGAUAAAUAUGUAAAGUAUAUAUUUUUCUUACGACCUUGUAAUACAGAUAUAAUGAACCUAUUUUAUUGUCAAAAAGCAAUCAGUACUCAUUCAAUACCUUCUGUGUGUCCAGGUUCUUCUAAGGAACUAUUCUUUUUGUGAGGAACUUUCUAUGGAAGCUGGUUGGCCCACAGCUUUUGCAGAUGAUCUGCUGCCCUGAGUACACUCUAAUGACCAAGACCACAAGUGGGCCCCUAACUCAUCUAGGUAGGACUUUGCUAUAAAACACGUGACCCUAGGGAAACUUUUGAAGUUAGCGGUAUAGAGAGUACCACCACCAGACGCCACCAUGCCUGCGGAAGGAGGAAAAACGGACAUGGAAAGGAUUGGCCUCUUUAGUGAGAUGGAAUAUAUUACUGUGGGUGAUAAAUAUGUGUCACAAUUUAAUCGACCCUUUAAUGAGGCUGCAAGCAAAAAUAAACAGAUGCUACCUGGAGGGUCCAAAGAAAUGUCAGAUCUUCAGGCAGGUUAUUUUGAUCCCCAUUUUGUAAGGAUUUUUGAAGGUGAAGGCUACAUAAAUCUGAAUCAAGUGAGGAGACGGGAUAUGGUGGAAGCAGCCAAAAAAAAUCUAGGCAAAGCAUUCCUCCCUAGUAAUGGAGAGAAAAAGCCAUGUGGCUUAGGAAGCUACUAUGGAACAAUAGGUGGUCCAGUCCCAUUUUUCAGCGCACAGUCAAAACCUCGAGAAAAAUACAAGGCACCUGGAAAGAAUUUAUACACAAACCCGGGAAAGAAAGGAACUGGAUAUGGCUAUGCAAAUAUUACCAUAGGUAAACAGUUUUCACACUCUGCCGACUUCUAUGAUGCAGCAAAACUAAAGUAUAAGAAAGCGAAUGAAGAGCACCAUCGUUUACUUAAAGGAGCACCAUUUAAGUUAAAUCUUCACCCAAGGGACUAUUUUGACGCUAAUCCUUAUUUUUCUGAGGAAUCUUUACCACCAAUUAAAAAAGAAGAGAAGAAGAAAACAAUUUCAAAUACUUUUAAACCGUCUUCUCCUGGUAAAAAGCCUGGUGGAAUGAAGGCAGGAACAUUUGAUCCUUACCCAUCACAUUCUGCUGACCCUUAUGUGGCUAAAUUGGCAAAUAUUUCUGGCAAAGAUGAUAAGAUUUUCCACCCACCAAGUGGACCAAAAAGCAGACCAGUUGAAAGUAUAAUGACUUUGAAUGUCAGAAGGGCACUAAAUUCAAAGAACUACAAGACUUCUUCAGUACCAUCCUAUUAGCAACUGGAAGACAAGUAGCUUUCUAGAUCUUAACUAUGAGUAAUUCACUAUCAAGAGCUAAUUAUUUGAAAAAAUAUAAGAUGUUAUGGAGCAGAUAGCUCAAGCAGUUAAAAGAAAUUCUGCAACUCUAAUUCUCUUCCUUAUUUUAAUACUACUAGUUAAUAAAUAGUAUUUGCUAAUAA